GGAAGUCAGACUAUGGGGCGGUGCGGCAGCGCGAAGCCUGCAGUCCUAAAGGCGGGGUCGCUCCAGGCUUCCGAGGGGGUGUGUCUCCCGCCUCUUUAACCUGGCAGGGGCGGUUCAAGUGGCCGGGGAAAUCGGCGAAUUGCAGGGUCAAGGGCUGGUGCUUUGAAAGAGAGGCGGAGGGGAGAGAGGGAUUUUCCCGUCCCCGCUGCGCUCCGUCCUCCAUUACUCGUUUUCUCCGCCCGCGGCCCGAACCCGUUGUGCGGUAGAGGCAGCCGGGUCCCUUUAAGGCCCAGCUGCGCUCCGUCCUCCAUUACUCCUUUUCUCCGCCCGCGGCCCGAACCCGUUGUGCGGUAGAGGCAGCCGGGUCCCUUUAAGGCCCAGCUGCGCCUGUGCCUUGGGCUCUCCUGACACGGCCCAUCCGGACCCUGAGGAGCCAGCGGGCCGCAAGCAAGUUGCUGGGCGGCGGUUGAGAUAGCGGCGGUGCUGGGAGGGGUAGGUGAGGGUCGCGAGGCUGCCUGAGCUUCUGAGUGAGCCUGGUGAUUUUGGGAACGCGGGACGGGCGACCUGCGGCGCCAGGAGCGGGGCCGAGGUACGGCGGCACGGCUGCAGCCUGGAUGGGAAGUUCAAGUUUACUGCGAAGUCCACCCAGCGUUCCGGAGGUGAGGGCGCCGCGCCAGGCCGGGCGGCAGGCAUUCUGAAGGCAAAUCCUGUUUAGACCCAGGCAAAGGUUCCUGGUGACCCAGGCUCUCAUGAGCAGAUUGUCCCUUAUCAUUCUCCUGAGGAUGUCUGGAGCUUCAGUGCUGUGUGCUCUUGGCCUCCACACUGGGGGUGCCACCAACUCCCACUGUCCAGGGCUUCUGGUGGACUCUCCGAGGCACCGAUGUAGAAACUUACCCAUUCAGUGCACCAAGAGCAGCCUCACAUGGUGUGGGCCGACAUGAAGAGCUGCCAGAUCCAACAGUUCUCAGAAUUCUUCAUAUAUUUUGGACAGCAGUUUUUCCAUCAGAUUAUUUUAAAUGUGAUUGAUAACAGUAAAGCCACACUCCUCAAGUGCCUGAAAUACCCCUCAUUGUCUUCUUCAGGUGGCAAGGGCUCUGGAACAGCCACAUAAAGCCCUUGAAGAUAAGGAUGGUCAAACAAAAUAAUAUCAUACCUGGAGAAACUCAGAUCUUGCUAAGAUUUACUGGUUGGGAAUCCAAAGUUAAUGCCAAGAAGCAGCUGCCAGUUGGGAUCAAAUGUGAGCCUAUGGAUCAAGACGGUUACCUGGCACGCUGGCCACAAUCUACCUCACUCUUAUCAGAGUCUGAGCAGUGCUUUCAGCUCUGAGUUGAGGCACCUCGAACCUUGUUUUUGUGGUGAAGGAUCCUAAAGUGCUGUGGGGAGUGAUCACAUUUUUCACAACAUCCCUGACUCCACCUCUUCUGCCACAAACGUCAGCAUGGUGGUAUCAGCCGGCCCUUGGUCCAGCGAGAAGGCAGAGAUGAACAUUCUAGAAAUCAACGAGAAAUUGCGCCCCCAGUUGGCAGAGAACAAACAGCAGUUCAGAAACCUCAAAGAGAGAUGUUUUCUAACUCAACUGGCCGGCUUCCUGGCCAACCGACAGAAGAAAUACAAGUAUGAAGAGUGUAAAGACCUCAUAAAAUUUAUGCUGAGGAAUGAGCGACAGUUCAAGGAGGAGAAGCUUGCAGAGCAGCUGAAACAAGCUGAGGAGCUCAGGCAAUAUAAAGUCCUGGUUCACUCUCAGGAACGAGAGCUGACCCAGUUAAGGGAGAAGUUACGGGAAGGGAGAGAUGCCUCCCGCUCAUUGAAUGAGCAUCUCCAGGCCCUCCUCACUCCGGAUGAGCCGGACAAGUCCCAGGGGCAGGACCUCCAAGAACAGCUGGCUGAGGGGUGUAGACUGGCACAGCAACUUGUCCAAAAGCUCAGCCCAGAAAAUGAUGAAGAUGAGGAUGAAGAUGUUCAAGUUGAGGAGGAUGAGAAAGUACUGGAAUCAUCUGCCCCCAGGGAGGUGCAGAAGGCUGAAGAGAGCAAAGUCCCUGAGGACUCACUGGAGGAAUGUGCCAUCACUUGUUCAAAUAGCCACGGCCCUUGUGACUCCAUCCAGCCUCACAAGAACAUCAAAAUCACAUUUGAGGAAGACAAAGUCAACUCAACUGUGGUUGUAGACAGAAAAUCCUCUCAUGAUGAAUGUCAGGAUGCUCUAAACAUUCUCCCAGUCCCUGGCCCCACCUCUUCUGCCACAAACGUCAGCAUGGUGGUAUCAGCCGGCCCUUUGUCCAGCGAGAAGGCAGAGAUGAACAUUCUAGAAAUCAAUGAGAAGUUGCGCCCCCAGCUGGCAGAGAAGAAACAGCAGUUCAGAAGCCUCAAAGAGAAAUGUUUUGUAACUCAACUGGCCGGCUUCCUGGCCAAGCAGCAGAACAAAUACAAAUAUGAAGAGUGCAAAGACCUCAUAAAAUCUAUGCUGAGGAAUGAGCUACAGUUCAAGGAGGAGAAGCUUGCAGAGCAGCUGAAGCAAGCUGAGGAGCUCAGGCAAUAUAAAGUCCUGGUUCACUCUCAGGAACGAGAGCUGACCCAGUUAAGGGAGAAGUUACGGGAAGGGAGAGAUGCCUCCCGCUCAUUGAAUGAGCAUCUCCAGGCCCUCCUCACUCCGGAUGAGCCGGACAAGUCCCAGGGGCAGGACCUCCAAGAACAGCUGGCUGAGGGGUGUAGACUGGCACAGCACCUUGUCCAAAAGCUCAGCCCAGAAAAUGAUGAAGAUGAGGAUGAAGAUGUUCAAGUUGAGGAGGAUGAGAAAGUGCUGGAAUCAUCUUCCCCCAGGGAGAUGCAGAAGGCUGAAGAAAGCAAAGUCCCUGAGGACUCACUGGAGGAAUGUGCCAUCACUUGUUCAAAUAGCCACGGCCCUUGUGACUCCAACCAGCCUCACAAGAACAUCAAAAUCACAUUUGAGGAAGACAAAGUCAACUCAUCUCUGGUUGUAGACAGAGAAUCCUCUCAUGAUGAAUGUCAGGAUGCUCUAAACAUUCUCCCAGUCCCUGGCCCCACCUCUUCUGCCACAAACGUCAGCAUGGUGGUAUCAGCCGGCCCUUUGUCCAGCGAGAAGGCAGAGAUGAACAUUCUAGAAAUCAAUGAGAAGUUGCGCCCCCAGCUGGCAGAGAAGAAACAGCAGUUCAGAAGCCUCAAAGAGAAAUGUUUUGUAACUCAAGUGGCCUGCUUCCUGGCCAAGCAGCAGAACAAAUACAAAUAUGAAGAGUGCAAAGACCUCCUAAAAUCUAUGCUGAGGAAUGAGCUACAGUUCAAGGAGGAGAAGCUUGCAGAGCAGCUGAAGCAAGCUGAGGAGCUCAGGCAAUAUAAAGUCCUGGUUCACUCUCAGGAACGAGAGCUGACCCAGUUAAGGGAGAAGUUACGGGAAGGGAGAGAUGCCUCCCGCUCAUUGAAUGAGCAUCUCCAGGCCCUCCUCACUCCGGAUGAGCCGGACAAGUCCCAGGGGCAGGACCUCCAAGAACAGCUGGCUGAGGGGUGUAGACUGGCACAACACCUUGUCCAAAAGCUCAGCCCAGAAAAUGAUAACGAUGACGAUGAAGAUGUUCAAGUUGAGGUGGCUGAGAAAGUGCAGAAAUCGUCUUCCCCCAGGGAGAUGCAGAAGGCUGAAGAAAAGGAAGUCCCUGAGGACUCACUGGAGGAGUGUGCCAUCACUUGUUCAAAUAGCCAUGGCCCUUAUGACUCCAACCAGCCACAUAGGAAAACCAAAAUCACAUUUGAGGAAGACAAAGUCGACUCAACUCUCAUUGGCUCAUCCUCUCAUGUUGAAUGGGAGGAUGCUGUACACAUUAUCCCAGAAAAUGAAAGUGAUGAUGAGGAAGAGGAAGAAAAAGGGCCAGUGUCUCCCAGGAAUCUGCAGGAGUCUGAAGAGGAGGAAGUCCCCCAGGAGUCCUGGGAUGAAGGUUAUUCGACUCUCUCAAUUCCUCCUGAAAGGUUGGCCUCAUACCAGUCUUACAGCAGCACAUUUCACUCAUUAGAGGAACAGCAAGUCUGCAUGGCUGUUGACAUAGGCAGACAUCGGUGGGAUCAAGUGAAAAAGGAGGACCAAGAGGCAACAGGUCCCAGGCUCAGCAGGGAGCUGCUGGCUGAGAAAGAGCCUGAAGUCUUGCAGGACUCACUGGAUAGAUGUUAUUCAACUCCUUCAGUUUAUCUUGGACUGACUGACUCAUGCCAGCCCUACAGAAGUGCCUUUUACGUAUUGGAGCAACAGCGUGUUGGCUUGGCUGUUGACAUGGAUGAAAUUGAAAAGUACCAAGAAGUGGAAGAAGACCAAGACCCAUCAUGCCCCAGGCUCAGCAGGGAGCUGCUGGCUGAGAAAGAGCCUGAAGUCUUGCAGGACUCACUGGAUAGAUGUUAUUCGACUCCUUCAGGUUAUCUUGAACUGCCUGACUUAGGCCAGCCCUACAGAAGUGCUGUUUACUCAUUGGAGGAACAGUACCUUGGCUUGGCUCUUGACGUGGACAGAAUUAAAAAGGACCAAGAAGAGGAAGAAGACCAAGGCCCACCAUGCCCCAGGCUCAGCAGGGAGCUGCUGGAGGUAGUAGAGCCUGAAGUCUUGCAGGACUCACUGGAUAGAUGUUAUUCAACUCCUUCCAGUUGUCUUGAACAGCCUGACUCCUGCCAGCCCUACAGAAGUUCCUUUUAUGCAUUGGAGGAAAAACAUGUUGGCUUUUCUCUUGACGUGGGAGAAAUUGAAAAGAAGGGGAAGGGGAAGAAAAGAAGGGGAAGAAGAUCAAAGAAGAAAAGAAGAAGGGGAAGAAAAGAAGGGGAAGAAGAUCAAAACCCACCAUGCCCCAGGCUCAGCAGGGAGCUGCUGGCUGAGAAAGAGCCUGAAGUCUUGCAGGACUCACUGGAUAGAUGGUAUUCGACUCCUUCAGUUUAUCUUGGACUGACUGACCCAUGCCAGCCCUACAGAAGUGCCUUUUACGUAUUGGAGCAACAGCGUGUUGGCUUGGCUGUUGACAUGGAUGAAAUUGAAAAGUACCAAGAAGUGGAAGAAGACCAAGACCCAUCAUGCCCCAGGCUCAGCAGGGAGCUGCUGGCUGAGAAAGAGCCUGAAGUCUUGCAGGACUCACUGGAUAGAUGUUAUUCGACUCCUUCAGGUUAUCUUGAACUGCCUGACUUAGGCCAGCCCUACAGAAGUGCUGUUUACUCAUUGGAGGAACAGUACCUUGGCUUGGCUCUUGACGUGGACAGAAUUAAAAAGGACCAAGAAGAGGAAGAAGACCAAGGCCCACCAUGCCCCAGGCUCAGCAGGGAGCUGCUGGAGGUAGUAGAGCCUGAAGUCUUGCAGGACUCACUGGAUAGAUGUUAUUCAACUCCUUCCAGUUGUCUUGAACAGCCUGACUCCUGCCAGCCCUACAGAAGUUCCUUUUAUGCAUUGGAGGAAAAACAUGUUGGCUUUUCUCUUGACGUGGGAGAAAUUGAAAAGAAGGGGAAGGGGAAGAAAAGAAGGGGAAGAAGAUCAAAGAAGAAAAGAAGAAGGGGAAGAAAAGAAGGGGAAGAAGAUCAAAACCCACCAUGCCCCAGGCUCAACAGCGUGCUGAUGGAAGUGGAAGAGCCUGAAGUCUUGCAGGACUCACUGGAUAGAUGUUAUUCGACUCCAUCAAUGUACUUUGAACUACCUGACUCAUUCCAGCACUACAGAAGUGUGUUUUACUCAUUUGAGGAACAGCACAUCACCUUUGCCCUUGACAUGGACAAUAGCUUUUUUACUUUGACGGUGACAAGUCUCCACCUGGUCUUCCAGAUGGGAGUCAUAUUCCCACAAUAAGCAGCCCUUACUAAGCCGAGAGGUUUCAUUCCUGCAGGCAGGACCUAUAGGCACCUGAAGAUUUGAAUGAAACUAUAGUUCCAUUUGGAAGCCCAGACAUAGGAUGGGUCAGUGGGCAUGGCUCUAUUCCUAUUCUCAGAGCAUGCCAGUGGCAACCUGUGCUCAGUCUGAAGACAAUGGACCCACGUUAGGUGUGACACGUUCACAUAACUGUGCAGCACAUGCCGGGAGUGAUCAGCCGGACAUUUUAAUUUGAACCAUGUAUCUCUGGGUAGCUACAAAAUUCCUCAGGGAUUUCAUUUUGCAGGCAUGUCUCUGAGCUUCUAUACCUACUCAAGGUCAGUGUCAUCUUUGUGUUUAGUUCAUCCAAAGGUGUUACCCUGGUUUCAAUGAACCUAACCUCAUUAUUUGUGUCUUCAGUGUUGGCUUGUUUUAGCUGAUCCAUCUGUAACACAGGAGGGAUCCUUGGCUGAGGAUUGUAUUUCAGAACCACCAACUGCUCUUGACAAUUGUUAACCCACUAGGCUCCUUUGGUUAGAGAAGCCACAGUCCUUCAGCCUCCAAUUGGUGUCAGUACUUAGGAAGACCACAGCUAGAUGGACAAACAGCAUUGGGAGGCCUUAGCCCUGCUCCUCUCAAUUCCAUCCUGUAGAGAACAGGAGUCAGGAGCCGCUGGCAGGAGACAGCAUGUCACCCAGGACUCUGCCGGUGCAGAAUAUGAGCAAUGCCAUGUUCUUGCAGAAAACGCUUAGCCUGAGUUUCAUAGGAGGUAAUCACCAGACAACUGCAGAAUGUAGAACACUGAGCAGGACAACUGACCUGUCUCCUUCACAUAGUCCAUAUCACCACAAAUCACACAACAAAAAGGAGAAGAGAUAUUUUGGGUUGAAAAAAAGUAAAAAGAUAAUGUAGCUGCAUUUCUUUAGUUAUUUUGAACCCCAAAUAUUUCCUCAUCUUUUUGUUGUUGUCAUUGAUGGUGGUGACAUGGACUUGUUUAUAGAGGACAGGUCAGCUCUCUGGCUCAAUGAUCUACAUUCUGAAGUUGUCUGAAAAUGUCUUCAUGAUUAAAUUCAGCCUAAACUUUUUGCUGGGAACACUGCAGAGACAAUGCUGUGAGUUUCCAACCUCAGCCCAUCUGCGGGCAGAGAAGGUCUAGUUUGUCCAUCACCAUUAUGAUAUCAGGACUGGUUACUUGGUUAAGGAGGGGUCUAGGAGAUCUGUCCCUUUUAGAGACACCUUACUUAUAAUGAAGUACUUGGGAAAGCGGUUUUCAAGAGUAUAAAUAUCCUGUAUUCUAAUGAUCAUCCUCUAAACAUUUUAUCAUUUAUUAAUCCUCCCUGCCUGUGUCUAUUAUUAUAUACAUAUCUCUACGCUGCAAAUUUUGGGUCUCAAUUUUUACUGUGCCUUUGUUUUUACUAGUGUCUGCUGUUGCAAAAAGAAGAAAACAUUCUCUGCCUGAGUUUUAAUUUUUGUCCAAAGUUAAUUUUAAUCUAUACAAUUAAAACCUUUUGCCUAUCACUCUGGACUUUUGGAUUGUUUUUUACAUUCAGUGUUAUAAUAUUUGAUUAUGCUGAUUGGUUUUGGUGGGUACUGAUGUGAAUUAAUAAAAACAUUUCAUUUCCA